CCAGGAGUUGCAAGCUGCAGUGAGCUAUGAUUGCACCACUGCUCUCCAGCCUGGGCAAUGGAACGAGACUGGAGACAUGCAGUGGGAGGGGAGAGCCAUCAGGACUUCCGGAGCAUCAAAGCAAAGUUCCAGGCCUCUCAGCCGGAGCCCAGCGACCUGCCCAAAAAACCUCCGAAGCCUGAGUUUGGUAAACUGAAGAAGUUCUCCCAGCCUGAGCUAAGCGAGCACCCCAAGAAGGCCCCGCUGCCUGAGUUUGGUGCAGUGUCCUUGAAGCCCCCGCCGCCUGAGGUCACUGACCUCCCCAAGAAGCCCCCGCCGCCUGAGGUCACUGACCUCCCCAAGAAGCCCCCGCCGCCUGAGGUCACUGACCUCCCCAAGAAGCCCCCGCCGCCUGAGGUCACUGACCUCCCCAAGAAGCCGUCCAAACUGGAGUUGAGUGACCUCUCCAAGAAGUUCCCACAGCUGGGGGCCACUCCGUUUCCAAGGAAGCCCCUGCAGCCUGAGGUCGGUGAGGCCCCUUUGAAGGCCUCGCUGCCGGAGCCUGGUGCGCCGGCCCGGAAACCCCUGCAGCCCGACGAACUCAGUCACCCCGCCAGACCCCCCUCCGAACCCAAAUCCGGCGCAUUCCCCAGGAAGCUCUGGCAACCCGAGGCCGGUGAGGCUACCCCGAGGUCCCCGCAGCCUGAGUUGAGUACCUUUCCCAAGAAGCCUGCGCAGCCUGAGUUCAACGUGUACCCCAAAAAGCCUCCGCAGCCUCAGGUCGGUGGCCUCCCUAAGAAGUCCGUGCCGCAGCCUGAGUUCAGCGAGGCCGCUCAGACUCCCCUCUGGAAGCCUCAGUCCAGCGAGCCGAAGCGCGACUCCAGCGCCUUUCCCAAAAAGGCCUCCCAGCCUCCGCUGAGUGACUUUCCCAAGAAGCCUCCGCAGCCUGAGCUUGGGGACCUCACCAGGACCUCCUCAGAGCCCGAAGUCAGCGUGCUUCCCAAGAGGCCGCGGCCGGCCGAAUUCAAAGCGCUCUCCAAGAAGCCCCCGCAGCCCGAGCUGGGCGGCCUCCCCAGGACCUCCUCAGAGCCCGAGUUCAACUCACUCCCCAGGAAGCUGCUGCAGCCGGAGCGCCGGGGGCCACCCCGCAAGUUCUCACAGCCUGAGCCCAGCGCUGUCCUCAAGAGACACCCGCAGCCUGAGUUCUUCGGUGAUCUCCCUCGAAAGCCUCCACUCCCCAGCUCCGCUUCCGAGAGCUCACUGCCUGCGGCCGUGGCCGGCUUCAGCUCCCGGCACCCGCUCAGCCCUGGGUUUGGAGCGGCUGGGACACCCCGCUGGAGGUCAGGAGGCCUGGUUCACAGUGGAGGGGCCAGGCCAGGCCUCAGACCCAGCCAUCCACCCCGGCGGAGGCCUCUGCCCCCUGCCAGCAGCCUGGGACACCCUCCAGCCAAGCCCCCGCUGCCCCCGGGGCCCGUGGAUAUGCAGAGCUUUCGGAGACCCUCUGCAGCAUCCAUAGAUCUACGGAGGACCCGCUCGGCCGCUGGGCUCCACUUCCAGGACCGACAGCCUGAAGACAUCCCGCAGGUCCCAGAUGAGAUCUACGAGCUGUAUGACGAUGUGGAACCCAGAGAUGACUCCAGCCCCAGCCCCAAGGGCAGAGAUGAAGCGCCCUCAGUUCAGCAAGCCGCCAGGAGGCCACCACAAGACCCAGCGCUCAGGAAGGAGAAGGAUCCCCAGCCACAGCAGUUGCCACCCAUGGACCCAAAGUUGCUGAAGCAGCUGAGGAAGGCAGAGAAGGCCGAGAGGGAGUUCCGGAAGAAGUUCAAGUUUGAAGGGGAGAUCGUGGUUCACACGAAGAUGAUGAUCGACCCCAACGCUAAGACACGUCGCGGGGGUGGCAAGCACCUCGGGAUCCGGCGCGGGGAGAUCCUGGAGGUGAUCGAGUUCACCAGCAAUGAGGAGAUGCUGUGCCGGGACCCCAAAGGCAAAUAUGGCUACGUGCCCAGAACAGCGCUCCUGCCCCUGGAGACGGAGGUGUACGAUGAUGUCGACUUCUGCGGUACGUGGACACUCUGGGAGGGCUGGAGGGACCCUGGCGAUUCCCCGGGGGCGCUGCUCACUAUUGGGCUUCUGGGGAGAGGGGUCCAUGGAAGUCACGCUUCCUCGGCAGAUCCCCUGGAAAACCAACCACUCCCCCUGGGACGGUAAGACCGGUAGGCGUGGGGCCAGGACAGCCAGCCAGCCCAGCGCCCGCUCACCCAGGAGCCCUGGAUCCCGGCGCGGGAAAGUCACAGAGCUGCCUGGGCUUGUACCUGGCCACAUAAAGCCCCAGUUUAAAGCA